GUGUUCCUGGUCUGCGGCAGCCAUGCUGAACUCGUAUGGAGAGGCGAGUGGGGGGGACAGAGUCCAGGACCGCGGGAUAGGAAGCUGGGGAUAUGGACAAGCAGCAGCGUUAUAGCGCUCUGGGUUUCGGGACAUAGGCCUGGGCCAUGCGGCCCCCUUGGCCCCUUGGCGCGACCCCCAGGAACGUUCGGAAAGCUGGUCCUCGUGGCUGGGGGAAAGGCGGGGGGUGGGGGGGAAGCGGGCACGUGACCCCGGUCAGCCAAUCUGGGUGCUGCUGACGUGGCCGCGCGGCCCCGAUGCUCUCCCCACCCCCCCAGCCCGUUCGGGAAGGGAGGGGCUGGGGGCUACGCCCCCUCCCCCAGCACGGCUUCGUUUUCUGGGGGGGGGUUGACACCCCGGAUUACAUACCCCGUACCAAGCCGAGGGCAACUUUGGAGGCCCCCUGGAAGGCUUUAGGAUCCAGAUUCUUCGCUGCUGCUGCCUUACCGCCGAGAACCACCACCCGCCAGGCGUCUUGCGGCCACACCCCUGGCGGGUUCAGGCAGGCUACGCCCACGCGACCCCUCCCGUUUCCCUGCUUUGGCCAAUGGAGGAGCUACGAAUGGCACGACCUGCUCGAGCUUGGCAGUCUCCAGUUGGGCUGUGCAUGGAAGCUUGGGAAGACUUUGUUGGAAGGGGAGGCGGGGAGAGAGUGCUGGAGGCUCUGGGGCGAUGGCUUCCGCACCUCUUCCAACCACCCUCUUUCCCUGGAGUCGGCGGACCACAGCUCAGCCAAUUGGCUUGGAGAUGUGGCGGGUUGCCACUUCCCUGUGGGUCUCUGCGGCACUCUUCUGCCUGGUGACUGACACCUUGGAAAUGAAGUUUAUGACGUCAUCGUUGCGGCUGGCCAAUAGAAAAAGCUCCCGCGGAGAGGUGUUCCUUCCCCUUCGACUCAGCUUCUUCACCCGCGUGAGCGAGCGCGCGCGCGCGGAGGGGGUGGGGAAAAUCUCAAGCAGGGUGGCGCGCAUGAGCGGCGAAGCUCCUCCUCCCCGCCUAUAUAUAAAGGGCUGGCGCGGGGCUCGGCGGCGCCAUUUCGUGCUGGAGUGGAGCAGCCUCUAGAACGAGCUGGAGGAUUCUGCCUACCGAUACAGAGCCUUCGAGUCGUCCGGGGCCGCCAUUACAAUCCACCUCCAUCCGCUUGGAAAUGGCCUUCGUCCCGGCCUAUGACUGGUCCCAGCGGGCAGUACAGACCCCCUAGAAGCCCCUGGAGCUCCCCUUUUUCGGGCCCCGCCCAAUCCUCGGAGUCUGUCCACCCCCUCUACUCCGCCCUCAAGAGGAUUUCAAAGAUGGAGGCGGCGGCUCCCUAAACCACUUUUCGUGUUCAUCCGCCUCCAUCCGAGAUCGAAACGGGACCUCGUCGGCCCCGUAGGGGCCCGACAAGAAGAGGGAAUCCCUGCAGACCAACAGCGGGCUAUAUUGACGACGGUGUCUGAGAUCGGGGACCGUCUUUUGAAGAGUCAGUCCCUCCUUAGUUGCCCGCCUCAGCUGAGGCCGCCGCCAUUUUCUUGCUGUCCGCCGUCUGCAGAGCGCGCCAAGCUGCCCGGAGCUCUCCGAGAGGCCCCAAAGAGACUGCUUUCGUGCCGGCCAGGCAGGGGGUUUGUCGCCUGGAGGCCCAAGAGGAACGGCCUCCCCCCAACUUAGCGGGUUAUGCUGGACCGGGCGGUGAGGGGAACCGAGGCCACCCGGACUUUCCGCGGCUGAGGGCAGCGCCGGUUCCUUGCGGUCAAGAUGCUGCAAAACGUGACUCCCCACAAUAAGCUCCCUGGGGAAGGGAAUGCAGGGUUGCUGGGGCUGGGCCCAGAAGCAGCAGCACCAGGGAAGAGGAUUCGAAAACCCUCUCUCUUGUAUGAGGGCUUUGAGAGCCCCACAAUGGCUUCGGUGCCUGCUUUGCAACUUACCCCUGCCAACCCACCACCCCCGGAGGUGUCCAAUCCCAAAAAGCCAGGACGAGUUACCAACCAGCUGCAAUACCUACACAAGGUAGUGAUGAAGGCUCUGUGGAAACAUCAGUUCGCAUGGCCAUUCCGGCAGCCUGUGGAUGCUGUCAAACUGGGUCUACCGGAUUAUCACAAAAUUAUAAAACAGCCUAUGGACAUGGGUACUAUUAAGAGGAGACUUGAAAACAAUUAUUAUUGGGCUGCUUCAGAGUGUAUGCAAGAUUUUAAUACCAUGUUCACCAACUGUUACAUUUACAACAAGCCCACUGAUGAUAUUGUCCUAAUGGCACAAACGCUGGAAAAGAUAUUCCUACAGAAGGUUGCAUCAAUGCCACAAGAAGAACAAGAGCUGGUAGUGACCAUCCCUAAGAACAGCCACAAGAAGGGGGCCAAGUUGGCAGCGCUCCAGGGCAGUGUUACCAGUGCCCAUCAGGUGCCUGCCGUCUCUUCUGUGUCACACACAGCCCUCUAUACUCCUCCACCUGAGAUACCUACCACUGUCCUCAACAUUCCCCACCCAUCAGUCAUUUCCUCUCCACUUCUCAAGUCCUUGCACUCUGCUGGACCCCCGCUCCUUGCUGUUACUGCAGCUCCUCCAGCCCAGCCCCUUGCCAAGAAAAAAGGCGUAAAGCGGAAAGCAGAUACUACCACCCCUACACCUACAGCCAUCUUGGCUCCUGGUUCUCCAGCUAGCCCUCCUGGGAGUCUUGAGCCUAAGGCAGCACGGCUUCCCCCUAUGCGUAGAGAGAGUGGUCGCCCCAUCAAGCCCCCACGCAAAGACUUGCCUGACUCUCAGCAACAACACCAGAGCUCUAAGAAAGGAAAGCUUUCAGAACAGUUAAAACAUUGCAAUGGCAUUUUGAAGGAGUUACUCUCUAAGAAGCAUGCUGCCUAUGCUUGGCCUUUCUAUAAACCAGUGGAUGCUUCUGCACUUGGCCUGCAUGACUACCAUGACAUCAUUAAGCACCCCAUGGACCUCAGCACUGUCAAGCGGAAGAUGGAGAACCGUGAUUACCGGGAUGCACAGGAGUUUGCUGCUGAUGUACGGCUUAUGUUCUCCAACUGCUAUAAGUACAAUCCCCCAGAUCACGAUGUUGUGGCAAUGGCACGAAAGCUACAGGAUGUAUUUGAGUUCCGUUAUGCCAAGAUGCCAGAUGAACCACUAGAACCAGGGCCUUUACCAGUCUCUACUGCCAUGCCCCCUGGCUUGGCCAAAUCGUCUUCAGAGUCCUCCAGUGAGGAAAGUAGCAGUGAGAGCUCCUCUGAGGAAGAGGAGGAGGAAGAUGAGGAGGACGAGGAGGAAGAAGAGAGUGAAAGCUCAGACUCAGAGGAAGAAAGGGCUCAUCGCUUAGCAGAACUACAGGAACAGCUUCGGGCAGUACAUGAACAACUGGCUGCUCUGUCCCAGGGUCCAAUAUCCAAGCCCAAGAGGAAAAGAGAGAAAAAAGAGAAAAAGAAGAAACGGAAGGCAGAGAAGCAUCGAGGCCGAGCUGGGGCCGAUGAAGAUGACAAGGGGCCUAGGGCACCCCGCCCACCUCAACCUAAGAAGUCCAAGAAAGCAAGUGGCAGUGGGGGUGGCAGUGCUGCUUUAGGCCCUUCUGGCUUUGGACCUUCUGGAGGAAGUGGCACCAAG